AGUCCGCGGUCCUCACCCGCGCCGGGCGGUAGUAGUAGCUGUGCUCUUUGGGGUCCAGGCGCCGCGGCGGGAUGUAGCUGAAGGCGGACUGCGCCGAGACGGGCGGCGGCCUGGGCUUGCCCCGCAGCGUGGACGCGGUGGUCUCCUCCUCGUCGUCCUCCAUGCCGCCACCGUCCAGCGCCCCCGCCUUGGCCGCGGUCCGUCCCGCCCGCCCAGGGGCCCAGUCGGAGUCUGCAGGCCUCAGGUUGCUCAGCGCCAGCGUCUAGCCCGCGUCUGUGUUCGGUCGUUGCCUGGAAACCGCCGCCUGGCGACCCGGAGCUGCCCUGCAGCAUUCCCGCUCCAGGGUGGAGCGACCCUCCCCUCCUCCCUCCCGGCCCCUCGACUACACCUGGGGUCUCUCCUUCCUUCCUCCUCGGGAGGAGCCCGACUGGGAGACGCCGCGGGGACUACCCAUUUCCAGCCCGCUCACCUUUCCCAUGCAGCAGCCCCUGCUUCACUCACUGAUCACUCCUUCGCGAGACCAUUAGUGACUGAGCACCUAGCGCAUGGUGUGUCAGGAGCUGGAGAUUGAGCCUUGAACGGAGCAGGCCUUGUCCACAGGAAGCUUACAGUCUGGAGAAGACACAUGAAAGACGCGAAGAAGCCAAAUGACUUGCCGAGGCUCCAGGGCAGCGCUGUCCAAUAGAAACAUGAUGAGAGCCACGUGUGUCGUUUCUUAUUUGACUCAGAGGAACUGACUGCUUCCGUUUUCCCAGAAUUCUAUCAAAUAUCUUUCAAGUGUCCACAUGUACCCAAGCGACGCACAUUCCUCACAUAGAGGAAGGCAAGGAAAGAAUCAUAUCUAUUUUUUUCACCUUCUUGAGAAAAAGAUACCGCUGCUUAUUAGCCUCAACGAGUCUUGUAAUGUGAAAAACACAACAUUUUCCUGUACCUUUUAUGGAUAUCUUCAUUAGCUGUGGAUGGCAAUACAAAUCCUUCUUCAUCUAAUUUAAUUUCAACAUCUGGUGAGAGAAGAAAGGAAAAAUUCCUCGUGUGAUACCCUCACAAACACUAUCUUCCUGUAUUCAUUCCUUUGCUUUGCUUUGAUUCCUUCCACCUUGCAUUGAUCAAUUGGACUGAAGGCUGCAAAGUAAUGACCACAACCAAACAAUGGUGGCAGAGAUCCUUCAAUCCAGACUGUGAAGAAAACCCUUGAGUUAAGACAUUAGACAUCUGUGCAACUCAUAACUUCCAUCAUUCCAACUUGCAGUGCCUCCAUGUUUCACUGUUACAUGCCUUGAAGUGAUGAGGAGGUUUCUGUUACUAUAUGCUACACAGCAGGGACAGGCAAAGGCCAUCGCAGAAGAAAUAUGUGAGCAAGCUGUGGUACAUGGAUUUUCUGCAGAUCUUCACUGUAUUAGUGAAUCCGAUAAGUAUGACCUAAAAACCGAAACAGCUCCUCUUGUUGUUGUGGUUUCUACCACGGGCACCGGAGACCCACCCGACACAGCCCGCAAGUUUGUUAAGGAAAUACAGAACCAAACACUGCCGGUUGAUUUCUUUGCUCACCUGCGGUAUGGGUUACUGGGUCUCGGUGAUUCAGAAUACACCUACUUUUGCAAUGGGGGGAAGAUAAUUGAUAAACGACUUCAAGAGCUUGGAGCCCGGCAUUUCUAUGACACUGGACAUGCAGAUGACUGUGUAGGUUUAGAACUUGUGGUUGAGCCGUGGAUUGCUGGACUCUGGCCAGCCCUCAGAAAGCAUUUUAGGUCAAGCAGAGGACAAGAGGAGAUAAGUGGCGCACUCCCGGUGGCAUCACCUGCAUCCUCGAGGACAGACCUUGUGAAGUCAGAGCUGCUACACAUUGAAUCUCAAGUCGAGCUUCUGAGAUUCGAUGAUUCAGGAAGAAAGGAUUCUGAGGUUUUGAAGCAAAAUGCAGUGAACAGCAACCAAUCCAAUGUUGUAAUUGAAGACUUUGAGUCCUCACUUACCCGUUCGGUACCCCCACUCUCACAAGCCUCUCUGAAUAUUCCUGGUUUACCCCCAGAAUAUUUACAGGUACAUCUGCAGGAGUCUCUUGGCCAGGAGGAAAGCCAAGUAUCUGUGACUUCAGCAGAUCCAGUUUUUCAAGUGCCAAUUUCAAAGGCAGUUCAACUUACUACGAAUGAUGCCAUAAAAACCACUCUGCUGGUAGAAUUGGACAUUUCAAAUACAGACUUUUCCUAUCAGCCUGGAGAUGCCUUCAGCGUGAUCUGCCCUAACAGUGAUUCUGAGGUACAAAGCCUACUCCAAAGACUGCAGCUUGAAGAUAAAAGAGAGCACUGCGUCCUUUUGAAAAUAAAGGCAGACACAAAGAAGAAAGGAGCUACCUUACCCCAGCAUAUACCUGCGGGAUGUUCUCUCCAGUUCAUUUUUACCUGGUGUCUUGAAAUCCGAGCAAUUCCUAAAAAGGCAUUUUUGCGAGCCCUUGUGGACUAUACCAGUGACAGUGCUGAAAAGCGCAGGCUACAGGAGCUGUGCAGUAAACAAGGGGCAGCCGAUUAUAGCCGCUUUGUACGAGAUGCCUGUGCCUGCUUGUUGGAUCUCCUCCUCGCUUUCCCUUCUUGCCAGCCACCACUCAGUCUCCUGCUCGAACAUCUUCCUAAACUUCAACCCAGACCAUAUUCGUGUGCAAGCUCAAGUUUAUUUCACCCAGGAAAGCUCCAUUUUGUCUUCAACAUUGUGGAAUUUCUGUCUACUGCCACAACAGAGGUUCUGCGGAAGGGAGUAUGUACAGGCUGGCUGGCCUUGUUGGUUGCUUCAGUUCUUCAGCCAAACAUACAUGCAUCCCAUGAAGACAGCGGGAAAGCCCUGGCUCCUAAGAUAUCCAUCUCUCCUCGAACAACAAAUUCUUUCCACUUACCAGAUGACCCCUCAAUCCCCAUCAUAAUGGUGGGUCCAGGAACCGGCAUAGCCCCGUUUAUUGGGUUCCUACAACAUAGAGAGAAACUCCAAGAACAACACCCAGAUGGAAAUUUUGGAGCAAUGUGGUUGUUUUUUGGCUGCAGGCAUAAGGAUAGGGAUUAUCUAUUCAGAAAAGAGCUCAGACAUUUCCUUAAGCAUGGGAUCUUAACUCAUCUAAAGGUUUCCUUCUCAAGAGAUGCUCCUGUUGGGGAGGAGGAAGCCCCAGCAAAGUAUGUGCAAGACAACAUCCAGCUUCAUGGCCAGCAGGUGGCGAGAAUCCUCCUCCAGGAGAACGGCCAUAUUUAUGUGUGUGGAGAUGCAAAGAAUAUGGCCAAGGAUGUACAUGAUGCCCUUGUGCAAAUAAUAAGCAAAGAGGUUGGAGUUGAAAAACUAGAAGCAAUGAAAACCCUGGCCACUUUAAAAGAAGAAAAACGCUACCUUCAGGAUAUUUGGUCAUAAAACCAGAAAUUAAAGAAAGAGGAUUAAGCUUUUUUGACUGAAAGUACUAAAAGUCAGCUUUACUAGUGCCAAACCUUUAAAUUUUCAAAAGAAAAUUUUCUUUCAACAUUUCUUGAAGGACAUGGAGUGGAGAUUGGAUCAUUUAACAAUAUAACAAAACUUCCUGAUUUGAUUUUACGUAUCUUCUAUCUACGCCCUUCCUGUGCCUGUGACUCUCCCCAAAUUGCCCUGUUGCCUUGAGCUCUUCUGAGCUAAGGCAGCCUUCAGUCCCUAUCAGCGCCUCCUUUACUUCCCAGAGAACUUCACAGAGACUCUGUCCUUCCAUGCAAAGGCUUCCUGAAAUAGGGAGACUGACUGAGUAGCUCAUUCUUGUGACUUACAGUGCCAACAUUUAAAAAAGUAUGAAAAUGAUUUAUUUUUAUAUGAUGUAUACCCAUAAAGAAUGCUCAUAUUAAUGUACUUAAAUUACACAUGUAGAGCAUAUCUGUUAUAUGUUUAUGUAACUAUCAAAUGGUUAUUUGUUACUAAAGCUAUAUUUCUGAUAAAAAAUAUUUUAGGAUAAUUGCCUACAGAGGGAUUUAUUUUUAUGAUGCUGGAAAUAUGAAAUGUAUUUUAAAAUUUCACUCUGGCAUAUGAUUUAUCUAUCACCAUUACUUUUUUUUAAGUCACAAUUUCAGAAUUUUGGGACAUUUGCAUUCAAUUUACAGGUACCAGUACGUACAUAUUUUAAUAGAAAGAUACAACCUUUUUAUUUUCACUCCUUUUAUUUCUGCUGCUUGGCACAUUUUUGAGUUUUCCCACAUUAUUUGUCUCCAUGAUACCACUCAAGCAGUGUGCUGGACCUAAAAUACUGACUUUAGUUAGUAUCCUUGGAUUUUUAGAUUCCCAGUGUCUAAUUCCCUGUUAUAAUUUGCACAAACAAAACAAAAUGUUAUGAUAAUCUUUCUCCACUGUUCUAAUAUAUAUUGUAUUUUUAUUUGAUAGCUUGGGAUUUAAAACAUCUCUGUUGAAGGCUUUUGAUCCUUUUGAGAAAUAAAGAUCUGAAAGAAAUGGCA